GUAGUCCGGGCGCGCGAUUCACAGCGCCGCGUGCGCCCCGGGCGCGCCGUAGCCGCGGGGCCCGGGCCGGGCGCUACGCUACGAAGGCAGCGUAAGGCGGGCGCCGGACGCGGGCAGGGGCCGGGGCCGGAGCCGGGUCGGGGCGCCCCGCGGCUGAGGAGCGGGAGGCCGUCCGGGCAGCGCGGCCGGCGGCGAGAGGGGCCCCGCCGCUCUCCGGAGGCAGAAGUUGUGGAUCGGCCGGCGGGGGCGAGCGGGCCCGGGGGCCGGGGCCGCGCUGCCCGGGCCGCGAGGACGAGGCGGCGCCGCCGGGCUGUGGAGG